CCUCCCAGUCUCCCCCCACCACCCGUGCACGACUUCCUCACCACCCCCAGGUUCCCUGCAGAUGUCGUGUGUGUCCUGAGUGUUUCUUUGGUUCUUUGCACGCCAAGUCUCUUGGUUGUACCAUGUGACACACCCUGUGCACUGGUCGCUGUCUUCGUGGCUUCCACCCUUGUUAAUGAUGCUCCUGCCUCUGCCUCCCAGCCCCUCACCCAGCACAGCUCUGCCUGGACUUGGAGAGAUGGGAGGCAGACCCCCACCACCAUACAUGCUGUCUGUGGCCCCUCAGACAUUCUGUUUCAUCUCCCAUUCAUCUCCCUCCUCCCACCGUGUCAGUUUUUCUGCCUUUCCCUGCUCUGUUCUUCCCCCUCCUUAGGCCCCAGCCUGGGCCCAGACCCAUCCUCCCAGCCAGGUUUCCCUCCAGCAGGCUCCUUCCCUCCCUGUCACCUCCCUCUCACCAACCCGGGGUCUGAGCCCCUCAUUCCUGACCGUCCGUGUUCUCAGGAGUGGUUGAGGACACAGGGCCCCAGCCCAGCCCUCUGCACCCCCCAGCCCGGCCAUCUGCGCCCCACAGCCCCUUUGGAGCUUUUCUCUUGUCCUCUCACUCCUUCCCAGAAGUUUUUGCACAGAACUUCAUUUUGAAAGUGUUUUUCUCAUUCUCCAUACCUCCCCCAAGCUCUCCUCCAGCCCUUCCCAGGGCUCAGCCCUGCUGUCCUGAGCGUCUCCUGGGCCAGAGAGAGGAGAUGGGGGUGGGAGGGACUGAGUUGAUGUUGGGUUUUUCAUUCAAUAAAUUGGUGAUUUCUUACCGACUGCCUUGGGCUUCUAUGCCCCCUCACUGUGCCACAGGAGCUGCCCAACCCCUUUUCCACAGUGCAGCCCAACUCCAGUGAAAAUCCACCAGGAACGUAGGUGGAAAGAAGCGUACUCCCAUGUUCUCAAUCAUGGAAACAGGCAUGAAGGUGUCUCACCUGGCAUGAGGCAGGCAGAGGUCGGAAACAGGAAAGAUGUCAUUUCCACACCAAAAGCCCGUUUUUCCCCAGGACCCACCAUCCCCAAAUCCACCUCCCAAGGCAGUGACGUGUUGAGUGUGGCUUCCCCAUCUUCUGAUCAAAGGUCAGAACUUAGCUUCUCUCCCCUGCUCCAGGUUGGUGAAGUCCGAGCCAGUGGGGUCUUUGCCUCUGCAGGUGGAGGGAAUAGGGCUGAGGGACAUCUGUGGAGUUCCUUUUCCUGCCCGCCCUUGACUUAGAGAUGGAAAGCAGUGGUAGCCACUGUCCCCUGGGUGCCCGGUUUUUCCACUAGCUUCCAAGACAGGCCUGCACACACGAAGAAGUGUGUGCCUUCCCCAUGAAGAAGUGCCCAGAGGUGGCCAGGCACAGUGGCUCACGCCUGUAAUCCCAGCACUUUGGGAGGCCAAGGCAGGCGUUUUGCCCGAACUCAGGAGUUUGAGACCAGCCUGGGCAAUGUGGCGAAACCCCGUCUCUACUAAAAAAUAUAAAAAAUUGGCUGGGUGCGGUGGCUCACACCUGUAAUCCCAGCACUUUGGGAGGCUGAGGUGGGUGGAUCAUGAGGUCAGGAGAUUAAGACCAUCCUGGCCAACAUGGUGAAACCCCGUCCCUACUAAAAAUACAAAGAUUAGCUGGGUGUGGUGGCACGUGCCUGUAAUCCCAGCUACUCAGGAGGCUGAGGCAGGAGAAUCACUUGAACUCAGGAGGUGGAGGUUGCAGUGAGCCGAGAUCGCGCCACUGUACUCCAGCCUGGCGACACAGCGAGACUCCGUCUCAAAAAAAAAAAAAAAAUUUUUGCCGGGCGUGGUGGUAUGUGCCUGUAAUCUCAGCUACUCAGGAGGCUGAGGCACGAGAAUCACUUGAACCCGGGAGGCGGAGGUUGCAGUGAGCUGAGAUCGUGCCACCGCACUCCAGCCUGGACGACAGAAUGAGACUCUGUCUCAAAAAAGAGAAGUGUCCAGAGGUGAAGGCUUGCAGGAGAGGCAGCGCUUGGCAUCCUUGCCCUACAGGUAUAGCCCCAGAGGAGUGGAUGGCCAUCCAGAGCUUGCUGUCACUGGCCUCAGUCUUGGGUUCCCCAAGCCCUGUGCCCAGACGACCUCACAUAGAGAGGCUUGGGGACCCAGCUGUGUGGCCCUGCGCAAACUCUCUGAGCCUAGAAAAUGAAAAUCAUACCUGCCUUCUAAAUGAGGUGAUAGCGGGGCUGGUGAGAGGAAAGGCCAGGAGAAGCAAAUCAUACCUAGUGUGACCUGGAUCUAGGGUGUGAGUGUGGCUGCAGAGCAGGGUGAAGUGCCCACGAGGACUUCCCGGAGCACAGCCAGGCGAGGGCUGCAGGGCAGGAGCUGUGCAGAGCUGGGGGCCAGGGAGUUCCAGUGGAGGGGGUGGGACAAGUAGACUUGGAUCCCAGCUUCUGGCCCCCUUAGGUUCUGGCUUAGAGCUAGGAGAGAGGGUGAAGGGUGAACUCUCAGCCCGUCUGCAUCUGACACCAUAUCCUCAGCCUCCCCUUCUGUGGCAAUAAAUGCCCCACCCUGCUCCCAUCCUCGGGGCCCAUCCCUCUUCACUCCUUGAGGGCUUUUCUCCUACAGUCGCCCUCUCUCCUGCACUGCGGGUUCUCCCCUCUGCCAGGACUUUCCACCCACUUACAUGCAUCCCAAGUGGGUAUAGCUCAAUAUCAAAGACCAGAGACUUCCAGAUUCUCUUCAGCUGCCAUGCCUUGUCUCUGCUCCCCUUAGAGCAAAACUCUUCCAAAGAGCUGUGUGUGUUCCCCGUCUCCACUUCUGCCCACUCCCUUCCAGUUUUUUCCUCACAAUCCCACCAAAAGUUUCCUUUCCACAGUUGCCAGUGACCUGGGUUGCCCAGUCCUAUCAGUAGCAUUGGAUGCAAAUAAUCACCCGCUUGAGUCUUUCCACCUGGCCUGUGGACAGCUCUGUGCUCUCCUCUCACCUCCCUGGCCUCUCCUUUUUGGCCUCCCUUGCUAUGGUGUCCUCAGCUUCCCAGCCUCAAAACCCUGGAGGACUCGGGGCUCCAGCCUCUAAUAUAGCCUCCUCUCUCCCCACACUCAGCCCUAAAGGGAGCUCACUCGGCCCCAUGGUGUGAAAUGUGCUCCCCUGGGGAGACUUCCCUCCUAGUAAAUGCAAACUCGGUUCUUCAGUUCCGAGGCCGAAAACUGGGGAAUCCUCCUCGAUUCCUGUUUCUCUUGUACCCACCAUCUAAUCCAUGAGCAAAUCCUCCAGGCUUAUCCUGACAGUGCCUUGCCCCUUCCUCUACUGCGAUUAUCUCUUGUCUGGAUAUUGCAAUAGGCUCCUAAUUAUCCCUGCUCCCACCCUCUUCUCCCUGUAGCCUGUUCUCCACUCAAUAGCCAGAGAUUUUUCAGAGCUGAGCAGAUCGUGUUGGAUUGCUGAUCCAAACUGUGCAGAGUGUCCCACCUACCUAGGUGUGUAAGCUGAAGCCUUACCUGUGAGGGGCCCACAUGGUCUGAUCUCCCAGGAGCUGCUGGAUCUUAAUUCCUCUUACGCUUCCCCUCCUCACUGGCCUCUCAACAUUCCUCAAACACCACUCAGCCUCAGGGCCUUUGCACGGACCUUUGGUCCUGUCCAUCCUGCUGCUGCCCUCAGGCCCGUGUGGCUUGCUCCAUCAUUCAGGUCUUGGCUGAAAUGUCACCUCAGGAGGCCUUCCCUUCUCCAACCCCUCUUUUUUUUUUUUCUUACUCAUAUUUCCCACUCCUUGGCAUUAAUUAUUCAUUUGUCUCUCCCACAAGAAUGCAAGCUCCAAGAAAAGAGGAAAUGUUUUUCCCUGUUGUAUCCUUGGCACCCAAAAUACUGCUUGGCCCAUCACAGGUGCACAAUAAAUACUCGUUUGCAGAAUGAAGUUCCCUCUUGCUGCUGGAAUUGGGUUCCAAAUCCAGAUGUGCUACUCAAGACAUUUUAACUGAUGCCUUAGCCCAAAAGACACCUGGGUUUUCUCAUAGGCUCAGAAGUAAGAAGAUAGACUCCUACCCCGGGCAAAGAAGAGGAAAUCAGCUGUGUAGGGACAGUUUGGAGCACAAGGCAACUCAGGUGGAAGGUGCUGACUCAGACCCUGAAGCAGCUGUGCCCAGUCACCAGGAGUUAAGGCUGGACCAGAGCAGAGCUGCCCAAGGUCCGCCAGAGACUAAAGGCUUUUUGAUGCAGAAAGUGGAAGAGCCUCUAUCUAACCUGCACGCCAACUCCAGACUGGUUUUAUUUUUAAGUAAACUAUUUUAGAAUACCUUUAGAUUUAUGGAAAAGUUGCAAAAAUAGUAGAAAGAGUGGCUAUAUACCGCCCUGCCAGUUUCCCUUACUGUUAACAUGUUACAUUCAUGUGCAUUUGUCAUAACUAGUGAGUCAAUCGUGAUGCACGAUUAUUAACUAAAGUCCCUAUUUUGGCCGGGCACGGUGGUUCACUCCCAUAAUCACAGCACUUGGGGAGGCUGAAGCAGGUGGAUCAUCUGAGGUCAGGAGUUCAAGACCAGCCUAGCCAAUGUGGUGAAACCCCAUCUCUACUAAAAAUACAAAAAUUAGCCAGGCGUGGUGGGCACCUGUAAUCGCAGCUACUCGGGAGGCUGAGGCAAGAAAAUCGCUUGAACCCGGGAGGCGUAGGUUGCAGUGAGCCAAGAUUGCACCACUGCACUCCAACCUGGGCGACAGAGUGAGACUCUUUCUCAAAUAAAUAAAUAAAUGUCCCUAUUUUAUGCAUGUCCUUAGUUUUUCCCUAAUGUCCUUUCUCCAUUUCAGACUCCCACCCAGAAUGCCACACUACGUUUGGUCAUUCUGUCUUCUUUUUUGUUGUUGAUUUUAGAGACCAGGUCUUGCUCUGUUGCCCAGGCUGGAGUGCAGUGGUGCCAACCUAGUUCACUGCAGCCUGGAACUCCUGGGCUCAAGCCAUUCUCCUACCUCAGCCUUCUGGGUAUCUGGGACUACAGGCAUGUGUCAUUACACCUGGCUCUUUGUUUUGUUUUGUUUUCUUUCGUUUUUUUUGGUAGAGAUAGGGUCUUGAACUGACCUCAGUUAUCGAUCCUCCUACCUUGCCUCCCAAAGUGCUAGGAUUACAGGCGUGAACCAACACAUCCAGCCCAUUCUGCCUUCUUAGGAUCCUUUGGGCUGUGACAUUUUCUUAGACUUUUUGAUCUCUAUUUUUGAUGACCUUGACAGUUUUGAGGAGUAUUGGUCAGGCAUUUUGUAGAAUGUCCCUCAGUUGGGGAUUGUCUGAUGUUCUUCUCGUGGCUGGAUGGAGGUUAUAGGUUGUGGGGAGGAAGACCUCAAAGGUGAAUGCCCUUCUCAGCGCAGCCUGUGAAGGGCACAUGCCGUCAACAUGACAUCAUGGAUGAGGUUGACCUGGGCUCCUCACUGUAAAGUCCCACACACCUGCUCCCAUGCUGUUCUCUUUGGAAGGAAGUUGCUGGUGCAGCCCACACUCGGGUGAGGUGUUGAUUAUCCCUACAUGCAUCAUCUGGGAUUCUGCUGUACAGGAGGUUUCAGACUAAUCUUUAAACUGCUUCUUUCGCCACCCCUUUCACCUGCCGUGUCCAAGGACUGACAGCAUUAAUAGCUGUCACCGUCACCUACAGGGCAUUGCCUUUGAGCCAGGCUGCUGCUGAGUGCCUUAUAUGGUUUAUUUCAUCGAGUCCUUAAAGCAGCCCUCCCUGUGAAAUCAAUUCUGCUGAUGCUUCCUUUUGCAAAGGAGGAAACCAAAGGUCAGAGCCUCCCCUCCCAACUCUAGAGCCUCCCAUCUAACCACUUAUGUUGCGACCUGAACACUCACAGUCAUCCCAGACUUCACAUGGCCAAAGCAAGACUCCUGAUUUCCCUUGAUCUUCCCCAGUCGGCAAUGGCACCAGCCUCCAUCCUGUUACUCCAGCCAGAAACCCGGACUCAUCCUGCGCCGCCCCUCCCAAUCCAUCAGCAACUCUUGUCCAUGCUGCCUCCCAAACGCUGUUUCCAACUAUAAGCCAGGGUACCUUCCUCGCAUAGAGUAUCCUUUGUCGUCCUAUCCUCCCAGUGCCCUCUGAAUAGAGGCCAACCACCGUCCACCAGGCCCGUGGUCUGGCUCACUACCUUCACUUCUAGUUGCUUUCCCCCUGCCAUGCUCACCACCCUCGAGCCACACCUGACCUUUCAGUGCUCACAUCCCUCUUCCAACCCCAGAGUAAGCUCCUUUUCCUUUAAGAUGUGGCCUUUGUAUCACCUCCUCCAAGAGCCUUCCCCAACCACCCCACCCAAAGCCUGGUUGUUAGCCUCUGUCUCUUCAGUCAUAGAGUUCACUAUUACCUGCAGCAAAUGUCUCUGUACCACAUUCGAAUGAGAGCUCCAGGAGGACAAAGACCCGAGCCGCCGGACUCAUUGUUGCAGUAUCCAGCACCCUGGCAUGCGGCGGACCCUCGAUAAAGGCCCGGCGCCCGCCUGCCCGCACCCUCGUCCUCACAGACGCCACAGCCAUGGCCAUGAUGGUGUUUCCGCGGGAGGAGAAGCUGAGCCAGGAUGAGAUCGUGCUGGGCACCAAGGCUGUCAUCCAGGGACUGGAGACUCUGCGUGGGGAGCAUCGUGCCCUGCUGGCUCCUCUGGUUGCACCUGAGGCCGGCGAAGCCGAGCCUGGCUCGCAGGAGCGCUGCAUCCUCCUGCGUCGCUCCCUGGAAGCCAUUGAGCUUGGGCUGGGGGAGGCCCAGGUGAUCUUGGCAUUGUCGAGCCACCUGGGGGCUGUAGAAUCAGAGAAGCAGAAGCUGCGGGCGCAGGUGCGGCGUCUGGUGCAGGAGAACCAGUGGCUGCGUGAGGAGCUGGCGGGGACACAGCAGAAGCUGCAGCGCAGUGAGCAGGCCGUGGCCCAGCUCGAGGAGGAGAAGCAGCACUUGCUGUUCAUGAGCCAGAUCCGCAAGUUGGAUGAAGACGCCUCCCCUAACGAGGAGAAGGGGGACGUCCCCAAAGACACACUGGAUGACCUGUUCCCCAAUGAGGAUGAGCAGAGCCCAGCCCCUAGCCCAGGAGGAGGGGAUGUGUCUGGUCAGCAUGGGGGCUACGAGAUCCCGGCCCGGCUCCGCACCCUGCACAACCUGGUGAUCCAAUACGCCUCACAGGGCCGCUACGAGGUAGCUGUGCCACUCUGCAAGCAGGCACUCGAAGACCUGGAGAAGACGUCAGGCCACGACCACCCUGACGUUGCCACCAUGCUGAACAUCCUGGCACUGGUCUAUCGGGAUCAGAACAAGUACAAGGAGGCUGCCCACCUGCUCAAUGAUGCUCUGGCCAUCCGGGAGAAAACACUGGGCAAGGACCACCCAGCCGUGGCUGCGACACUAAACAACCUGGCAGUCCUGUAUGGCAAGAGGGGCAAGUACAAGGAGGCUGAGCCAUUGUGCAAGCGGGCACUGGAGAUCCGGGAGAAGGUCCUGGGCAAGUUUCACCCAGAUGUGGCCAAGCAGCUCAGCAACCUGGCCCUGCUGUGCCAGAACCAGGGCAAAGCUGAGGAGGUGGAAUAUUACUAUCGGCGGGCACUGGAGAUCUAUGCUACACGCCUCGGGCCCGAUGACCCCAAUGUGGCCAAGACCAAGAACAACCUGGCUUCCUGCUACCUGAAGCAGGGCAAGUACCAGGAUGCGGAGACCUUGUACAAGGAGAUCCUCACCCGCGCUCAUGAGAAAGAGUUUGGCUCUGUCAAUGGGGACAACAAGCCCAUCUGGAUGCACGCAGAGGAGCGGGAGGAAAGCAAGGAUAAGCGCCGGGACAGCGCCCCCUAUGGGGAAUACGGCAGCUGGUACAAGGCCUGUAAAGUAGACAGCCCCACAGUCAACACCACCCUGCGCAGCUUGGGGGCCCUAUACCGGCGCCAGGGCAAGCUGGAAGCCGCGCACACACUAGAGGACUGUGCCAGCCGUAACCGCAAGCAGGGUUUGGACCCCGCAAGCCAGACCAAGGUGGUAGAACUGCUGAAAGAUGGCAGUGGCAGGCGGGGAGACCGCCGCAGCAGCCGAGACAUGGCUGGGGGUGCCGGGCCUCGGUCUGAGUCUGACCUCGAGGACGUGGGACCUACAGCUGAGUGGAAUGGGGAUGGCAGUGGCUCCUUGAGGCGCAGCGGUUCCUUUGGGAAACUCCGGGAUGCCCUGAGGCGCAGCAGUGAGAUGCUGGUAAAGAAGCUGCAGGGGGGCACCCCCCAGGAGCCCCCUAACCCCAGGAUGAAGCGGGCCAGUUCCCUCAACUUCCUCAACAAGAGCGUGGAAGAGCCGACCCAGCCUGGAGGCACAGGUCUCUCUGACAGCCGCACUCUCAGCUCCAGCUCCAUGGACCUCUCCCGACGAAGCUCCCUGGUGGGCUAAUGCUGAAGGGGCAGCCAGUCACCAGAGCGCCCACCUGGCACACCCCCCUCACCCCAGCCCUGCGCAUGGGCCUGCUGCUUGUCCCGCCUGUCUCUCCCACAGCCCCUGUCUUUUCUGUUCAAUCUCAGGGUAACCUUCUCCCUUGUCAUCUCAGCCUGAGCCCUGGAGGCUGGGCCUGCCCACUCCAGCUCCAUCCCUUAUUUAUUCCUUCCAGCAGGGCCCUCUUCCCUAGGUUCGGGCCAGCAGGAGGUGCCGGCUGGAGUCUCCACCAUAGACUCAGUGGCCUGGCCUCCCCAGACCCCAGAGCCAAGAACACUAAGCACUCGCCGGCCCUUCGGCACCCUCGCCCUCCCUCCCGACUCAACCCGGCCGUUGCUUCUGUAUAUAGAGAAAUAAGUUAUUGGCCGCGCGCCUCCCUUCAGUCCACGGUACUACCCGGGCCUCCCCUCGUCCCUCUUCUAGUGGUACCGCCCAGGCCUUAAUCACCCCCAUUCCGUGCGGUGGUAUCUCCCAGGCUCUACAUUCUCGGGAGCGGCGCCUCCCAAGGGGGUCCUGGGACCUUCUCGCGCUCCUCCUGGCCUCUGAGGGAUGCGUCCUACCCGCGCCAUCGCCCCGUGGCCCAGGACGGGGACCUCCCCUUAGUCCGUCCUCCCACCGCCGGGCCCUGCCCCGCAUCCCGGCCUUAUGCACUGCCCCUCCCACCCGGCCCCGCCCAGGCACGGCCGACCCCGCCCCGGGCACCGCCCACCGAGCCAUCCUGCCUCGCCUCCCCCCACGCCUGCAGCUUCUCGCGAGGGGCGGCGACGGUCCCCUGGUGGCAGGAGGGGCUCCCCCUGUUGCGGGUGAGGCGGCUGCUCUCAUAUUUUCAGAUGUUGCUGUAGAAAUAAAGACGGUUUAAAUCUGA